GUCGGUUCGGUCCGCUCUGGGCGUUAGCAAGUGAUCUCCAGCCAAGGCGGCCGCCACCCCUUGCACACAGCAGAAAAUGCAAAAUGACCCUCUGGGGCAGUGAGGGGCUGUGGCCCUCGGCCCCGGCCUGCCGCACCCCCUUCCCGCAGCUGGCGGCCGGCAGCGCCGAACAGGGUCCGGGUGCAGCCCCCUCCCGCCCCUCCGCUGAGGCGCCGGCCUGAACUGGGCGCGGGAACCAGGCCGCCCUCGGCGCCCAGCCUGCCCUAGUCCCGCGCGCCGCCCCCGCUGUGCCGCGCCCACAUGGGUCUGUGCUACAGUCUGCGGCCGCUGCUUUUCGGGGGCCCAGGGGACGACCCCUGCGCGGCCUCGGAGCCGCCGGUGGAGGACGCGCAGCCCGCCCCGGCCCCGGCCCUGGCCCCAGUCCGGGCGGCCGCAAGGGACACGGCCCGGACCCUGCUCCCUCGGGGCGGCGAAGGGAGCCCGGCAUGCGCUCGGCCCAAAGCAGACAAGCCGAAGGAGAAGCGGCAGCGCACCGAGCAGCUGAGUGCCGAGGAGCGCGAGGCGGCCAAGGAGCGCGAGGCGGUCAAGGAGGCGAGGAAAGUGAGCCGGGGCAUCGACCGCAUGCUGCGCGACCAGAAGCGCGACCUGCAGCAGACGCACCGGCUCCUGCUGCUCGGGGCUGGUGAGUCUGGGAAAAGCACUAUCGUCAAACAGAUGAGGAUCCUGCACGUCAAUGGGUUUAAUCCCGAGGAAAAGAAACAGAAAAUUCUGGACAUCCGGAAAAAUGUUAAAGAUGCUAUCGUGACAAUUGUUUCAGCAAUGAGUACUAUAAUACCUCCAGUUCCGCUGGCCAACCCUGAAAACCAAUUUCGAUCAGACUACAUCAAGAGCAUAGCCCCUAUCACUGACUUUGAAUAUUCCCAGGAAUUCUUUGACCAUGUGAAAAAACUUUGGGACGAUGAAGGCGUGAAGGCAUGCUUUGAGAGAUCCAACGAAUACCAGCUGAUUGACUGUGCACAAUACUUCCUGGAAAGAAUCGACAGCGUCAGCUUGGUUGACUACACACCCACAGACCAGGACCUCCUCAGAUGCAGAGUUCUGACAUCUGGGAUUUUUGAGACACGAUUCCAAGUGGACAAAGUAAACUUCCACAUGUUUGAUGUUGGUGGCCAGAGGGAUGAGAGGAGAAAAUGGAUCCAGUGCUUUAACGAUGUCACAGCUAUCAUUUACGUCGCAGCCUGCAGUAGCUACAACAUGGUGAUUCGAGAAGAUAACAACACCAACAGGCUGAGAGAGUCCCUGGAUCUUUUUGAAAGCAUCUGGAACAACAGGUGGUUACGGACCAUUUCUAUCAUCUUGUUCUUGAACAAACAAGAUAUGCUGGCAGAAAAAGUCUUGGCAGGGAAAUCAAAAAUUGAAGACUAUUUCCCAGAAUAUGCAAAUUAUACUGUUCCUGAAGACGCAACACCAGAUGCAGGAGAAGAUCCCAAAGUUACAAGAGCCAAGUUCUUUAUCCGGGACCUGUUUUUGAGGAUCAGCACGGCCACCGGUGACGGCAAACAUUACUGCUACCCGCACUUCACCUGCGCCGUGGACACAGAGAACAUCCGCAGGGUGUUCAACGACUGCCGCGACAUCAUCCAGCGGAUGCACCUCAAGCAGUAUGAGCUCUUGUGAGGAUGCUGCCGCCACCCUGCGACGGAGCGGCGCCCCGGACUGCCUGACUGCCAGCCCCAUGCCAUGGUAGGAGGCAGAGUCUCUAGUUCCAUCUCGCUGCCGUCUGUCCCGUUCUGUGUCGACCACCAAGCCUCUGGCUACCUCUGUCCCCUCAGGUUUGGUUGUGUAGCUUCUGUUGUCAUUGAAUACGGCCUCCCGCAGCAUCCCACCCCCAAACCACCGACUCUCAUUGCCGACACUGCAGCAGAAUCUCUCCGGGUGGGAGCCCCAUUAUUCAUUCUCCCUUUAUUGAUUCAUCGAGGAGAACUUGGUAGAUGGGGAGAAAACACAGUUGGUUUUUUUUUCCACGUUAUCAACCGUGACUGCAAGAGCGUUCGUGCAGUGCCCUGAGCCACGGCCGUCUCUGAUUCUCCCUUUAUGAAGCUGCAGGCUGACGAGAGAUGGUCCCUUCCCAUUGGCCUUAGCCCAAGACUUGGAGUCGACCCCAAGCGACAGAGUGACCAGAAACCCUUUUACAGUCACAUUCAGAGUCGCUGCUGGCCUCAGGCAUUUGAAUUAGAGCUACUUUGAGCCUCUUAGGCAGAAAACCUACCACAUUCACUACUGCAAAAUGUGUCCUGUCUAAAAAUGAUUCUCUAAACUUUCCCUAUACUUAGGCAUAGUCUUCUUUCUUAGAUUCUCUUUGUUGUUGUCCCUAUUGCUGGUUUAUUACACUGUACAGACCACAAAAUGUAAUAUUCUUUUGUAUAACUACUAAAGAAAAAUCCUUGUAGAUCUUUGUGCCUUCACCAUGGCUAUCUAUACCUGUACAUGAAAUGUGUUUGUAUUGUGCUGAAGAGCUUAAUGUCAACAUUACCUGCUGCUUACUCUGAAAAAAGGAAUGAAUGGUAGCUGUAGAAUUUAGGAUAUUUUAUCAGGUUGGCACUUUAUAAAAUACUCCCUGAUUUAAAAAAUUGUAAGUUAUACACGUUAAUCAUCCACAUUCUAUCGACAAUGUACCAACAUCACAAGCUGUUGCAACCACCUGCUGUUACUUCUCUGAGCUGUAAAAACCUGAACUCAAUUCAGGGGUACAAAUUGCAAUCUAAUCUUUUCAGGGAACCAGGGAUUUUUUUCUCUCUCUCUAGACAAUAUGUUUCCUCAUUAGUCUGCUAAUGAAACACUUCUUCAAGUUCCCCAAGUGGGAACAGGUCCAUCAUUCCCUUAGUCAAAACUUUGGACACAGGCUACGUCAUACAAGUAAGCAAACAGUAAGAGAAAAACAAAAUGUGGCCAGGCGCGGUGGCUCACGCCUGUAAUCCCAGCACUUUGGGAGGCCGAGGCAGGCGGAUCACGAGGCCAGGAGAUCAAGACCAUCCUGGCUAACAUGGCGAAACCCUGUCUCUACCAAAAAUACAAAAAUUAGCCAGGCGUGGUGGCGGGCACCUGUAAUCUCAGCUACUCGAGAGGCUGAGGCAGGAGAAUCUCUUGAACCUGGGAGGUGGAGAUUGCAGUGAGCCGAGGUCGUGCCAUCGCACUCCAGCCUGGACAUCAAAGUGAGACUCAGGCCAAAAAAAAAAAAAAAAAAAACCUUGACGUGUCAAUGUUUGUGUCUGGCCUAGGAGAAUGAGGAUGACAGCUUCACUUGCCUUUUGAAGAAGAAACAUUACAAAACCUUAAUCUGAAGUAUAAAGUCAAAAGAUACGGCUCUUUCUCACACUUGCAAGACUUACAAAUACAGCCUCAAACAUUAUGACACACCAACAAUAUCUAGAAAGUAAGAACUGGUGUAGCAAUGAUGCUUCAUAUUCUAGCUGUAGCCACAGAGUUGAGGGUAGUUUUUGUAGGUCUAAAAUAAUAAUCUAUAAAGAUGUCCAAAGUUAAAUUUUCAACAAUACAAAUCUAGAGAAGUGACAGCCUACAUUACUUCAUUAUUACUCUUCUUUUAGUCUUUAGUCUUUAAUAUUUUAAAGUUUACUCUAUAAAUCAGCAUUUUGUAAUCCUUUAUAAACUCAUCCAGAUUUAAAUGCUACUUUUUCAUGAAGAAAGGAUAACUUUAUAGACAGUCAGUGCAACACACACAUUUUAUCUCAUCACCGUCUUACUGCCUCCCCAUCCACUGUCUCAUAAAGCCCUCAGCUGAACUAAGAUAAAUAAUACAAUGGAAAUUAUUUUCAGUUCCCCUUGCACUGUCAAAGUAAAACAAGAAAACUGAAAAGCUGCACCCCCAGCAAGAAAGGGAAGUAUGCUGUUGUAUGCAUCAUUACUCAACAAUUACCCUCUAACUAAACAUCCUGUUUAAGAGUUUAAUUCAAACAACAGCCAGACUGUUAAGAAAAAAAACAAAAAGAAUAACUUUUAUCUGGCUUACAAUUAUUAAAGCAUUUAUUUUCAGGUACCAAAAGCCAUAUCCCAUUCCACUUUUUAAGUUUCUUUUGAUCACUGACAGGCAUUAACAGAUGUAGCAACGUGGUCUCCUAUAGAGAAAAUUACACUUAUCUAAAAAUCUGAUUCCAUUAAUUGAUCAAGUAUAAAAAUCUACGAAAACAAUAUGUUCUGCACAUCACAUCUGUACUUUUUUUUUUUUAAAUAUAUUUUUUGAGACGGAGUCUCACUCUGUUGCCCAGGCUGGAGUGCAGUGGCAUGAUCUUGGCUCACUGCAACCUCCGCCUCCCGGGCUCAAGGGAUUCUCCUGCCUCAGCCUCAGCUGGUAUUAUAGGCACUUGCUACCAUGCUUGGCUAAUUUUUGUAUUUCUAGCGGAGACGAGGUUUCACCAUGUUGGCCAGGCUGGUCUUGAACUCCUGACCUCAAGUGAUCCACCCGCCUCAGCCUCCCAAAGUGCUGGGAUUACAGGUGUGAGCCACUGUGCCCGGCCACAUCUGUACUUUUAAGGGUACAGCUUUACAGUACAUAGGAAUUUGAGAACCACUUCACAGGAAGAGGGAAACAGCCCAAUAUUUAUUUAUGUAUACACAUAAUCCCAAGUGUGUGCUGGGGCCACCAGGCCCUUCCUGGGGGAACAAGGACUGUCGUGCAUGUGAGUGACGACAUUAAUAGCAUUUACAUACUGUACAGAUGCAACCUUUGAUGAUACAUAUAUUUGAUAAAAAUGAGAAAACAGAUUUGUUGUAGAGUACCUGUCCACUUUUAUAGCAUGAGAACAGUACAAUCAACUAUUUAUUUUGCAGUUACUCAUUUCAGUGAUUGAGAAUUUCUGUGCUGUGCAGAGAGACGGCCUGUAAUUGGUCUCAUCAUCCACUUGAUUCUAACAUGAUCUCUGCCCAAAGUUCCAUUUCUUGGGCUUUGAUAUUUAUAAUGGCGCCUGCUCUUCAUCUUGUCUUACGCUUUCCGAGCAAGUUCAAACCAGAAAGAAAAGGUGAGGCUAGAAGCCCAAAGUGAGUGAGUGUGAGGACCACAAGGAAGCCCACCACUCCACAGUAGAUGAUCAAAACCACAUCCUCACGUGGGAGGUAGCACUUGGAGAGGGUGUAGUCUGUGGGCGUGAUGCUACCCUGGAAAGGAGAAGGGAAAGUUAUGCUGAGAGCACCAGGCACACGUUGAACACCGCAGUCUUAGAAACAGCAGAGGGAAGACUGCCUUCUCAGGUCCCCCUCAGGUGAGGCAGGGAACGGGCCCUCCUCACCUGAGACCAAGGGGGCCCAGCCUUCUCCCUGCACAGCUCACCCCCGACCAGCCCAGGCUCCAGCAGGAGAGACAAGUAAGGCCCAAGUGUGCCUGAGUGGAAAAUGUCUGGGACACUGACCUGUCAAAACUGGCCCCUGGCUCACUGGGUUCCCAUCAAAUAUAGUGGGGGAUCCAUAACAGAGAUUCAGAGAGGCACCGUGGAGUUCCAGGGUCAUCGGUCAGCGAGGAACAAGGAGGGAAAGGUGUCUUCCUGCCCCUUGAUGCUCAACUAAGCAUCUGUUCCCUAGAAAUACAUGUGUCCAGGUCGUCUCCAUGGGCUUUUCUUUGCAGAUACUUUUAUGUGGAACAACAGUGGCAAAUGUUUUCAUUUACUUUGAAUUUGAAAAUGUUAGGGUUUCCUCCACCUUUUUAUGAAGUAAAAGAACCUGUCGUACCAGCAUCAUGAGCUGGAUGCAGGAGCCCAUGGCUGAAAGGAGUUAAAACGCCCAGUGGUCAUUAAGUGAAACAUCUUUUAUCAACCUGCAAAAGCUGCAGCGUUCUCUGCCAGGUCAAAUGGGCAUGUUUAGAAAAUAAGAGAAGAUGGCUGAGUAUAGCUAAUGAAUAAAUGGUUGUUUCUUUAGAAAAUUAAACACACACAGAGUGUAAGAGGAGAGGAUACGGCCCUCCCUGAAGGAUAAAGUCCACCUGGACGGUGCCCUGCCCUCGCUUCUCACAUUAACUGCCCAGGAAUGUCAUGCUGAUUGGUUCCCGGAAGGGUGUUUGGCAAGGGGCAGUGUAUGGAGCUACGUGUAGAAGGAGAGAAAUUUGUGUGUGGCUUUUGUAAAUUUUGACCGAUUGCAGCAAUUAAAUAGUUGAUUACUGUGUUGAUUUAAAUACUUAUGAAAGCUUUCAGACAAAAAUAAACUUUCACGUUACCAUGAUGAAA